GCCAGUCCCUGGACAGCUACGACGCCAUGAAUAUCUUGCCCAAGAAGAGCUGGCACGUCCGGAACAAGGACAAUGUCGCCCGCGUGCGGCGUGACGAGGCCCAGGCCCGGGAGGAGGAGAAGGAGCGUGAGCGGAGGGUGCUGCUGGCUCAGCAAGAGGCCCGUACAGAAUUCCUACGGAAGAAAGCCAGACAUCAGAACUCACUGCCUGAGCUUGAAGCAGCAGAGGCGGGAGCCCCAGGUUCUGGCCCUGUGGACCUGUUUCGGGAGCUGCUGGAGGAAGGGAAAGGAGUGAUCAGAGGCAAUAAAGAGUACAAGGAAGAAAAGCGACAGGAGAAAGAGAGGCAAGAGAAAGCUCUGGGCAUCCUGACAUACCUGGGCCAGAGUGCAGCGGAGGCACAGACUCAACCCCCUUGGUACCAGCUACCCCCAGGGCGAGGGGGCCCCCCGCCCGGCCCAGCCCCAGAUGAGAAGAUCAAGAGCCGUCUGGACCCUCUGCGGGAGAUGCAGAAGCAUCUGGGGAAGAAGAGACAGCACGGCGGUGAUGAAGGCAGUCGCAGCAGAAAGGAAAAGGAGGGGUCUGAGAAGCAGCGACCCAAGGAGCCUCCAUCCCUGGACCAGCUUCGAGCUGAACGUCUGCGGAGGGAAGCAGCUGAGAGGUCUCGGGCAGAGGCCCUGCUGGCCCGGGUCCAAGGCCGGGCACUACAGGAGGGUCAGCCGGAAGAAGACGAGACGGAUGACCGGCGGCGGCGGUACAACUCCCAAUUCAACCCCCAGCUGGCCCGGCGCCCCCGCCAGCAGGACCCUCACCUUACUCACUGACUCCUGAGGGGGUACAGGAGAGGCCGCUGCUGCCAGCCGUCAUAUAAAACUAUUUAUUCAUAAAUAUUUUCCAAAAUGAAAAUAGGUUUACCAAAAAAUGUCCCUCACUGGGGAGGGGAGGAGGGGGCAGCCCUCGCCCCCGGGCCCCCAGGGUGGGGCUGAGAGGAAAACCUCCCGGCCCCCUCCCUGCUUCCUGGGAGAGGGGGAUGCCCCGUGGCUUGGGGCCUCCCUCCAGUCUUCCAGGGCAGGGCCCUCACCUGGGCAGGGGGAUCAGCAUGCGGGGGAAGGGGGUGGGUAGAGGGAGGGGCCGGUGUCACUGGAGGUCCCGGUCCUCCAGGUAGCGGUACUCAAAGGUGAAGCCUUCCUUCUUCCGCUGGCCCCACUUCUCGUAGUCAAAGUAGAUGUAGGUGCCCUGGCCGGGGGAGAAGGCGGUCAGUGAGUGGACGAGGAGGUGGUCUGGGAUCUGGGCCGGACCAACAGACAAAGGGGACAAUUCUUAGGGCUGUGGAUGUGUCAGGCACCGGGCCAGCUGCCCUGCACGCACACACUCUCAUCCAUCC